GAGACGUGCUCCUGGCACCGCCAGCUGCUACUUGGCCCUCGCCGGUGGCCCACCAGGACAAUGCCCCCCCGCAGCCAUCUCAUGCCCAUCGCCACUGCCCUGGGGCAGCUGAACUGAGCGUAUGUGCCACGCCGCCCAGGAGACCCCUCUGCUGCACCACUUCAUGCACCCCCGCUGCCUUGCCCCAGUGCUUCCUCGCCCUGGAGCUGGGCGCCAGCAUGGAGCUCACCCCUGCCUCUUCGCUGACUUGCUCCUUGCUCAGCCCGCGGCUGCCUGGCUCUUUCCCCCAGCUGCGGAGGGUUCCUCCUUGCAGCCGGCCCUGGCUGCCCAAGGCCCCCGUGAUGGCUCGCUGGCCUCCCUUCGGCCUCUGCCUCCUCCUGCUGCUGCUGUCCCCACCGCCACUGCCCUUGACAGGGGCCCAUCGCUUCUCCGCACCUAAUACCACUCUCAACCACUUGGCACUGGCACCUGGCCGAGGCACACUCUAUGUCGGCGCAGUGAACCGCCUCUUCCAGCUCAGCCCCGAGCUGCAGCUCGAGGCCGUGGCUGUCACUGGCCCUGUAAUCGACAGCCCUGACUGCGUGCCCUUCCGUGACCCAGCCGAGUGCCCACAGGCCCAGCUCACUGACAAUGCCAACCAGCUGCUGCUGGUGAGCAGCCGCGCCCAGGAGCUGGUGGCCUGCGGGCAGGUGCGGCAGGGCGUGUGUGAGACACGGCGCCUUGGGGAUGUGGCCGAGGUGCUGUACCAGGCUGAGGACCCUGGUGACGGGCAGUUUGUGGCUGCCAAUACCCCGGGAGUGGCAACGGUGGGGCUGGUGGUGCCCUUGCCCGGCCGGGACCUCCUGCUUGUGGCCAGAGGCCUGGCGGGCAAGCUGUCGGCAGGGGUGCCACCCCUGGCCAUCCGCCAGCUGGCCGGGUCUCAGCCCUUCUCCAGCGAGGGCCUGGGCCGCCUGGUGGUGGGCGACUUCUCCGACUACAACAACAGCUACGUCGGGGCCUUUGCCGACGCCCGCUCCGCCUACUUCGUGUUCCGCCGCCGCGGGGCCCGGGCCCAGGCUGAGUACCGCUCCUACGUGGCCCGCGUCUGCCUGGGGGACACCAACCUGUACUCCUACGUGGAGGUCCCCCUCGCCUGCCAGGGCCAGGGCCUCAUCCAGGCCGCCUUCCUUGCCCCGGGCACCUUGCUAGGGGUGUUUGCCGCGGGCCCAAGGGGCACCCAGGCGGCGCUCUGUGCCUUCCCCAUGGUGGAGCUGGGUGCCAGCAUGGAGCAGGCCCGGAGACUCUGCUACACGGCGGGCGGCCGGGGCCCCAGCGGCGCAGAGGAAGCCACCGUGGAGUACGGCGUCACGUCGCGCUGCGUCACCCUGCCCCUUGAUUCCCCCGAGUCGUACCCCUGUGGCGACGAGCACACCCCCAGCCCCAUUGCUGGCCGCCAGCCCCUGGAGGUCCAGCCUCUGCUGAAGCUCGGGCAGCCGGUCAGCGCCGUGGCAGCUCUCCAGGCAGAUGGGCACAUGAUAGCCUUCCUGGGGGACACCCAGGGCCAGCUGUACAAGGUCUUUCUCCACGGCUCCCAGGGCCAGGUUUACCACUCCCAGCAAGUGGGGCCUCCAGGCUCAGCCAUCAGCCCAGACCUGCUGCUGGACAGCAGUGGCAGUCACCUCUAUGUCCUGACUGCCCACCAGGUGGACCGGAUACCUGUGGCAGCCUGCCCCCAGUUCCCUGACUGUGCCAGCUGCCUCCAGGCCCAGGACCCGCUGUGUGGCUGGUGUGUCCUCCAGGGCAGGUGUACCCGGAAGGGCCAGUGCGGGCGGGCAGGCCAGCUGAACCAGUGGCUGUGGAGUUAUGAGGAGGACAGCCACUGCCUGCACAUCCAGAGCCUGCUGCCGGGCCACCACCCCCGCCAGGAGCAGGGCCAGGUCACUUUGUCUGUCCCCCGGCUGCCCAUCCUGGAUGCAGAUGAAUACUUCCAUUGUGCGUUCGGGGACUAUGACAGCUUGGCUCAUGUGGAAGGGCCCCACGUGGCCUGUGUCACCCCUCCCCAAGACCAGGUGCCACUUAACCCUCCAGGCACAGACCACGUCACUGUGCCCCUGGCCCUGAUGUUCGAGGACGUGACUGUGGCUGCCACCAACUUCUCCUUUUAUGACUGCAGUGCCGUCCAGGCCUUGGAGGCGGCUGCCCCGUGUCGCGCUUGCGUGGGCAGCAUCUGGCGGUGUCACUGGUGCCCGCAGAGUAGCCACUGCGUGUACGGAGAGCACUGCCCAGAGGGCGAGAGGACCAUCUACAGCGCCCAGGAGGUGGACAUCCAGGUGCGUGGCCCAGGGGCUUGCCCACAGGUCGAAGGCCUGGCAGGUCCCCACCUGGUGCCUGUGGGCUGGGAGAGCCAUUUGGCCCUACGCGUGCGGAACCUUCAACAUUUCCGAGGCCUGCCUGCCUCCUUCCACUGCUGGCUGGAGCUGCCUGGAGAACUUCGGGGACUGCCGGCCACCCUGGAGGAGACAGCAGGGGAUUCAGGCCUCAUCCACUGCCAGGCCCACCAGUUUUAUCCCUCCAUGUCCCAGCGGGAGCUCCCAGUGCCCAUCUACGUCACCCAGGGUGAAGCCCAGAGGCUGGACAACACCCAUGCUCUUUAUGUGAUCCUGUACGACUGCGCCAUGGGCCACCCGGACUGCAGCCACUGCCAAGCGGCCAACAGGAGCCUGGGCUGCCUGUGGUGUGCUGACGGCCAGCCUGCCUGUCGCUAUGGGCCCUUGUGCCCGCCGGGGGCUGUGGAGCUGCUGUGUCCUGCGCCCAGCAUUGAUGCAGUCGAGCCCCUGACCGGUCCCCCUGAGGGAGGCUUGGCCCUCACCAUCCUGGGCUCCAACCUGGGCCGGGCCUUCGCCGAUGUGCAGUACGCCGUGAGCGUGGCCAGCCGGCCCUGCAACCCUGAGCCCUCUCUCUACCGCACGUCGGCCCGGAUUGUGUGUGUGACAUCUCCUGCCCCCAAUGGCACCACUGGGCCCGUCCGGGUGGCCAUUAAGAGCCAGCCACCAGGCAUCUCAAGCCAGCACUUCACCUACCAGGACCCUGUCCUGCUGAGCCUGAGUCCUCGCUGGGGCCCCCAGGCAGGGGGCACCCAGCUCACCAUCCGAGGUCAGCACCUCCAGACAGGUGGCAACACCAGUGCCUUCGUGGGUGGCCAACCCUGUCCCAUCCUGGAGCCAGUGUGUCCGGAGGCCAUCGUGUGCCGUACCAGGCCCCAGGCUGCCCCAGGAGAAGCAGCGGUCCUUGUGGUCUUUGGCCAUGCCCAGCGCACACUGCUCGCCAGCCCCUUCCGCUACACCGCCAACCCCCAGCUUGUAGCGGCGGAGCCCAGUGCCAGCUUCCGGGGGGGUGGGCGACUGAUCCGUGUCAGGGGCACCGGCCUAGACGUGGUGCAGCGGCCCCUACUGUCUGUGUGGCUGGAGGCUGACGCAGAGGUGCAGGCUUCCAGGGCCCAGCCCCAGGACCCACAGCCAAGGAGGAGCUGUGGAGCCCCUGCUGCGGACCCCCAGGCUUGUAUCCAGCUCGGUGGGGGGCUGCUGCAGUGCUCCACCGUCUGCUCCGUCAACUCGUCCAGCCUCCUCCUGUGCCGGAGCCCUGCUGUACCAGACAGAGCCCACCCGCAGCGGGUCUUCUUCACCCUAGACAACGUGCAAGUGGACUUCGCCAGUGCCAGUGGGGGCCAGGGCUUCCUGUACCAGCCCAACCCCCGCCUGGCACCCCUCAGCCGCGAGGGGCCUGCCCGCCCCUACCGCCUCAAGCCAGGCCAUGUCCUGGAUGUGGAGGGCGAGGGCCUCAACCUGGGCAUCAGCAAGGAGGAGGUGCGCGUGCACAUCGGCCGCGGCGAGUGCCUGGUGAAGACGCUCACGCGCACCCACCUGUACUGCGAGCCGCCUGCGCACGCCCCGCAGCCUGCCAAUGGCUCCGGCCUGCCACAGUUCGUGGUGCAGAUGGGCAAUGUGCAGCUGGCCCUGGGCCCUGUGCAGUACGAGGCUGAACCCCCGCUGUCUGCCUUUCCCGUGGAGGCCCAGGCAGGCGUGGGCAUGGGUGCUGCAGUGCUGAUUGCCGCCGUGCUCCUCCUCACCCUCAUGUACAGGCACAAGAGCAAGCAGGCCCUGCGGGACUACCAGAAGGUGCUAGUGCAGCUGGAGAGCCUGGAGACCGGCGUGGGAGACCAGUGCCGCAAGGAGUUCACAGACCUCAUGACGGAGAUGACCGACCUCAGCAGCGACCUGGAGGGCAGCGGGAUCCCCUUCCUGGACUACCGCACCUACGCCGAGCGCGCCUUCUUCCCUGGCCAUGGCGGUUGCCCGCUGCAGCCCAAGCCUGAGGGGCCAGGGGAGGACGGCCACUGUGCCACUGUGCGCCAGGGCCUCACGCAGCUCUCCAACCUGCUCAACAGCAAGCUCUUCCUCCUCACGCUCAUCCACACCCUGGAGGAGCAGCCCAGCUUUUCCCAGAGGGAUCGCUGCCAUGUGGCUUCGCUGCUGUCGCUAGCGCUACACGGCAAGCUGGAGUACCUGACGGACAUCAUGAGGACCCUGCUGGGUGACCUGGCGGCCCAUUACGUGCACAGGAACCCCAAGCUCAUGCUACGCAGGACAGAGACCAUGGUGGAGAAACUGCUCACCAACUGGCUGUCCAUCUGCCUGUACGCCUUCCUGAGGGAGGUGGCUGGUGAACCACUGUACAUGCUCUUCCGGGCCAUCCAGUACCAGGUGGACAAAGGCCCCGUGGACGCCGUGACAGGCAAGGCCAAACGGACCCUGAAUGAUAGCCGCUUGCUGCGGGAGGACGUGGAGUUCCAGCCCCUGACGCUGAUGGUGCUGGUGGGGCCCGGGGCUGGCGGGGCCGCAGGCAGCAGCGAGAUGCAGCGCGUGCCAGCCCGGGUGCUCGACACGGACACCAUCACCCAGGUCAAGGAGAAGGUGUUGGACCAAGUCUACAAGGGCACCCCCUUCUCCCAGAGGCCCUCAGUGCAUGCCCUAGACCUUGAGUGGCGCUCAGGCCUGGCUGGUCACCUGACCCUAUCGGACGAAGACUUGACCUCCGUGACCCAAAACCACUGGAAGAGACUCAACACCUUGCAACACUACAAGGUCCCAGAUGGAGCAACAGUGGGGCUCGUCCCUCAGCUGCACCGUGGCAGCACCAUCUCCCAGAGCCUGGCCCAGAGGUGCCCCUUGGGAGAGAACAUACCCACGCUGGAGGAUGGCGAGGAGGGGGGGGUGUGCCUCUGGCACCUGGUGAAAGCCACCGAGGAGCCAGAAGGGGCCAAGGUGCGGUGCAGCAGCCUGCGGGAGCGCGAGCCAGCAAGGGCCAAGGCCAUUCCGGAAAUCUACCUCACCCGUCUGCUGUCCAUGAAGGGCACGCUGCAGAAGUUUGUGGACGACACCUUCCAGGCCAUUCUCAGCGUGAACCGGCCCAUCCCCAUCGCCGUCAAGUACCUGUUUGACCUUCUGGAUGAGCUAGCAGAGAAGCACGGCAUCGAGGACCCAGGGACCCUGCACAUCUGGAAGACCAACAGUCUGCUGCUGCGGUUCUGGGUGAAUGCCUUGAAGAACCCACAGCUCAUCUUUGAUGUACGGGUGUCGGACAAUGUGGACGCCAUCCUUGCUGUCAUCGCCCAGACCUUCAUUGACUCCUGUACCACCUCGGAGCAUAAAGUGGGCCGGGAUUCCCCAGUGAACAAACUGCUCUACGCCCGGGAGAUCCCACGCUACAAGCAGAUGGUGGAGAGGUACUAUGCGGACAUUCGCCAGAGCUCUCCGGCGAGCUACCAGGAGAUGAACUCUGCUUUGGCUGAGCUCUCCGGGAACUACACUUCUGCUCCCCACUGUCUGGAGGCUCUGCAAGAACUCUACAACCACAUCCACAGGUACUAUGAUCAGAUUAUCAGUGCCCUGGAGGAGGACCCUGUGGGCCAGAAGCUGCAGCUGGCCUGCCGCCUGCAGCAGGUCGCCGCCCUGGUGGAAAACAAAGUGACUGACCUGUGAGCUCUGGCUCAGACAGCAGCAAGCCGGAUCCACCAACACCGCAGCGCCUUAUGACCCCGGAACCGAGCCAGCCACUGAGGGGAGCUGGCAGAGCCUGGGGGCACAGGGUGCAAAGCCAGGCACUGUGCCCAGCAGUGGGCUCCCUGCCUGCCACCUCCCCUGCCAGCCCACCCACCUUCCCCCCACCUGAGAUUGUUUCUAAUUUAUAAGGAUCCCCCUCCUUCCCCCUCUCCCCAUUGUAUUUAUUUGCCUGCUGGAAAAUCACAUCCGGAAAUAAAAUAGAAAUAUGUCUUUUUAUUUUA